ACAGAUCUGAACCUGAUUUGUGUGUGCACCGCGUCUCCAGCGAUCCCGGAUCCACUGCGCUGCCAGGGGCCUGGGGGUGGGUCUCUUGCUGUCUCUGCGACGACAUCCUUACGUUUCGGCACUCUAAUGCUGGGUUUGUGCGUGUGUGUCUGCUUAGCGGUCUAGCGGGCUGUUAGGCUCCCUCGCCCCCAGCUCCUUGGCUCGCUCAGCUCCUCCACCGCAGCCCAGCAGUGAGACGCGCGCGCAGCCAGCUCCCCACGAGAUGGAACAGACCGAAGUGCUGAAGCCACGGACCCUGGCUGAUCUGAUCCGCAUCCUGCACCAGCUCUUUGCCGGCGAUGAGGUCAAUGUAGAGGAGGUGCAGGCCAUCAUGGAAGCCUACGAGAGCGACCCCACCGAGUGGGCAAUGUACGCCAAGUUCGACCAGUACAGGUGAGCGCGCUGCAGCUUCAAUGCCAGGCGGCGCCCACUCGCCCCGUCUGAGGAGGAAUGGACGUGGGGGACGCAGCCCAAAGUGACUGGCUCGGGAAGCUCGGGCCGCGCUGCGUCCGCCGCUCGCCCCCUCGCUGGCCAGCCGCGGGGCUGGCACGACUCGCUUGGGGCUCCGCGGCCACAGCGCAGGCGGAAGGUGGAUCCUACUGGCCUUGCUGACCUCCGGCCGGGAACGGCGGACAGGCGCCGGGAAGGGAGGCCACCGCGCGUCUGCGAGAUUUUCUGUUCUCUUCUCUCCCGCAAACCCCUCUGCUUCUAAACCACCAGUCCUCCUGCCCCUGGCCUCGGGAGCAAUGCCCACACUCCCAAGCCAUCGUUAACCCCGGGCGCGGAGAUGCGGAGAGACCGCACUCAGGUUCGGGCCCUCCUGACACCUUAAGGAACCGUCUGGCCGGACUAGCAGAGGGUGCUCCCAGGGGAGCACUACAUCAGCCAUCGGGAGAAGUGUGUGAUGUUGAAGAAGACAAGUCACCCGCGUCAGUUCUCCAUCACUGCGCCUUCGGUCGCCUGCAACCGGGCACCUUAUAGCAAGCAUUUUUACUCAUGUAAAAUAGCGUCUUGUGGCCGUCAGCUGCCACUACGGAAUUUCUGCUGUUCCCUUUCCCAAACCAAUUUAACUAACUUCCCCGACUGUGGGUUUAUUCAAAUCCACUGCCAAGUUUCGCAGAUUAAAUAUUCGACCGUCGUUUUUUUCAGCCCCCAAAUGAUCUGAUUUAUCUUAUCCUUGCUUCUGACGAUCUGUAAUGUAAAUUAAAGACCCCUACUUCCCAGAUGUACUUGAGUGAGGUGCCCUGGUAAGCUGGCUUUUUUGCAGCCCCGGCUUGGUGAUUAAGUCGAAUCUCUCUACCAAUCCUCCGGGGCCAGAGGUAAAAUUUAAUCACCCCGAAGUGUGAGAGGUUCUACUUUUUCUGAGCAGUUAGUGCGUCAGUCUUUGUGGUUUUUUGGGUUUAGGGUUAGGAGAAAGGGGUAAGUGAAAGAAAAGAAUAAGGAAAGAAGUAAGUUUGUUUUUCUUGGGAGCAGGUUCUUUUAGUCACUCUUCAACAUGUGGGAUGUUUCGUAAAGUUUUGUUGGCAUGGGCGGUUUCAACUGUAUUUUAGGAUUUGAAAUAGAAAAAGUGAAGACCACUAAGGAUCCCAUUUUUCAUAUACAAGUGACUUGAGGAAAUUCCUUUGGCUCCUAUCAGCUUAGUUCAUGGUAGAGCCCUUCUGUAGCCGUGAAAGCUAGCAGAGAGUCUAGCUUUUAAAUUUUCUUGCAUUUGCUCCAGGUAAUUGAAGACUUGUUAUGGGACAGGUACUCUUCCAGACACUUGACACAUAUGAGGAAUGGCAGGCAAUGAAGAAGUUGAAUGACUUGCACUAGGUCUUCUAUCGAUAGCGGCUCCAGGCUCCCGGGGUUAGCAUUGUUGUUCCAGAGCCUACACUCUAAACCACUGUUAAACCAGGACAGGUUGUAACAGUUUUUAAUCUUUAAUCUUUAGAACAAGUGUAUUUUCAAGGACCUUGAACUAGUCUCGAUUGACAAACUCUAAAGCUUUUGAAGUGCAACCAGCUGGGUUGAUCGGUCUUUUCACAGAUAUCUGAGGUGCCUAGCGCUGUGAAGGAUUCUGUUCUCUGACUUUGGGAGGGCCAGUGCAGAAGAAUCAAGACAGAAUAUGCUCCCGUGUGGGCCAGGCUGUGAAUUCUUUGAAAGAAGCUGCAGAGAAGCAACAAAGAUUAUCCUAAGACUUCUGGAGGAAGAAUUAGGAUCCUUCUGCAGGAACUCAGUUUACUGUGAAUUGAAGGUUGUGUACACAGCUUCUUGUUAGGUCAUAAAGGCUACAAAGUAGGGAAAACUGAGGCUAAAAAGCACUUACUAAGUAACUCCCUCUAGGAUCAUGCUCUUCGGACACCUCGGGGUGGGGAGGAAUGGGACAGGAUGGAAGGGGCAUGCUGGACAAGAGUUAACCGAUGACGAAGGGAAAAAAAACUCCCAAAAAAUGGAUCGUGGUCGUGGUUUGCAGUUUGUUGUUGGUGGUGGCAGUGGUGGUGGUUGGUUGUGGUAUACCCGAAAUCUUGUGGAUCAAGGAAAUGGAAAAUUUAAUCUGAUGAUUCUCUGUUGGGGUGAAGGACAUGGCAGCAGUAUUCAUGAUCAUACCAACUCCCACUGCUUUCUGAAGAUGCUACAGGGAAAUCUAAAGGAGACAUUAUUUGCCUGGCCUGACAAAAAAUCCAAUGAGAUGGUCAAGAAGUCUGAAAGAGUCUUGAGGGAAAACCAGUGUGCCUACAUCAAUGAUUCCAUUGGCUUACAUCGAGUAGAGAACAUCAGCCAUACGGAACCUGCUGUGAGCCUUCACUUGUACAGUCCACCUUUUGAUACAUGCCAUGCCUUUGAUCAAAGAACAGGACAUAAAAACAAAGUCACAAUGACAUUCCAUAGUAAAUUUGGAAUCAGAACUCCAAAUGCAACUUCGGGCUCGCUGGAGAACAACUAAGGGGCACCAAACCCUCUGAGGUUUUACUUUAAGGUUCGCUGUAUGUUUGCCUUGGACAAAAAGGCUACCUACCACGUGCUAUCCAGUAAUAUACUUAAAUAAGCCAAUACUUAGAUCUACUGUAAGGCAGAUGCUAAUUAUAAGGCAUUAAGUAAGCAAAUAGUGCCCUCAGCUACUGCAGAAGAAAAGUCCCACUGAGGAAAAGAAAGUCUUGUGAUUUUUAAAGGCAAGUUUUCAAGUGCUCUCAUAGUUCUAUCCUCUAAUUCCAUUAAAUCCAUACUAGGAGCGUCAGUGAGGGUUUUCAUAGCUUUUGGAAAUACUUUGGUCUCUGAACUGUAAUUAGCAAGAAGUAAAAACAGAAACGUCAAACGUCAAAUGUUUGCUUUGUUACCUGGAGGACUAAAUGUAGAUGUCUUUAGUAUACUUUGUAUGUUCUUAAUAUUGGAAGAUAAUUUUGUGAAUCUGUAGAUUUUAUUUUUUCAGUCUUACCUUACAAAUUUCUUUUCUAUGAAUAAUAGAGGAACUUACGGCACUCUGCCAUUUGUUAAUGAAAGGAAGUGCAGAGGAUUUAGAAAAGUACAUGAUCCCCAGACCACAACAAACCAAAACAUAAACUCAUGUCUGUGUCCCAUGGUCAUAGUCAAAGAUUUUGUACUGCUAAAAUUACCAAAUAAUUUAAAUAAAGUGGAUUUGAACACAA